CUUCCUCAGAGUAGGUUCGUGGUCUUGCUGACUUUAGGAAUGAAGCUGCAGACCCUCGUGGUGAGUGUUAACAGCUUAUAAAGGUAGUGAGGACCCAAAGAAUGAGCAGCAGCAAGAUUUAUUGUGAAGAGCGAAAGAACAAAGCUUCCACAGCGUGGAAGGGGACCCAAGUGGGUUGCCGCUGCUGGCUCGGGUGGCCAGCUUUUAUUCCCUUAUUUGGCCUCGGCCACAUCCUGCUGAUUGGUCCAUUUUACAGAGUGCCGAUUGGUGCGUUUUUACAGAGUGCUGAUUGGUGCAUUUACAAACCUUUGGCUGGACACAGAGCACUGAUUGAUGCAUUUUUACAGAGUGCUGAUUGGUGUGUUUACAGACUUUUAGCUAGACACAGAGUGCUUAUUGGUGUGUUUACAAUCCUUUAGCUAGACAGAAAAGUUCUCCAAGUCCCCACCCGACCCAGAAGCCCAGCUGGCUUCACCUCUCAAUCCGCCCUCUAAAUAGGAGACUCCAACUGCUGUUGGGAAUUGGGCAGUGACCGCUCUAGCUACUUCCUGCUGGAUAGGGAUGAAGAAGGGGCCCUGAAGUUGUAGUGUCCUCCAGAGGAGAACUAUUUAGGCUAGUGAAAGGGCCAGUGGGUUUGUCCAGGGGCCCUUGGUAGAAGUUGUUAGUUGAGCUCAUUUGGGGUUCCAUUUGUAAGACCAUCUGUAGCUUGAUAGCCUUGAUUCUAGAGGAAACACAUUUGAGGAGGUUAAAAAUACAGGGCCCGAAGGCGAGUAAUAGCAAGAUGGCUGCCACGGGACCUAGAAAGGGGAGAAGCCAUGUUGCCCAACUCCAGAGGUUCGUAUAAGAGUUUGAAAGGCAUUGUCUGACUUCAGAAGCCUUUUCCCGUAAACACCGGGCAGCAUCUCGUACUAUCCCUGACUGGUUAGUGUAAAAACAACACUCUUCCCCUAAGAAGGUGCAGAGUCCUCCUUUCUCAGCAGUGAGGAGGUCUAGGCCUCGGUGGUUUUGGAGAGUCACUGCUGCCAAAGAGUCUAUUUGGGAUUGUAGAGUAAGGAUAGAUUUCGUUAUUUCUUGCAAACUGAGAAAUCCUUUGAGAGUGUGUGGUAGUAGGAUAAUGAAGUAGAUAAACUGGCUACUCCGGUUCCUGUAGCAGUAGCCAUUCUUAACCCUAUAAGUAGGGGUAUUAGUUGUAUGGCUCUGCGAUGACAGACUUGAGCUUUGAGGGGUACUGAUAAAGUCUGAUUUCCUGAGGCAAUGUUAAUGUUGGGACUUAGAAAGACUAAGGUGCAGGUGCCUGUCCAGUUGGUGGGGAGGCAGAUAUAGGUCGAUGUUCCACAUAAGAAGAAUACAUCUUGGCUGGGUAGACAGAACUGGUUGUGUAUGUUAAAAAGGUGUGUGAGUUUGUUGUUUUCAUUUUCCCAUACUCCUAGAGUACUUGCCAAGGUAGCUCUGGUGAGUGGCUGGAAAGGGGUGUUGGGAGCAAACUGAGUGGCUCCCUGUGUUCUGUUUUCCCAUUGGAGAAAAAACUGUUUUGUAUCUACUAGGAACCAUUCAUUAGAGAGAGUGAUUGAAAGAGGGGAUGAGAAAGCAUUCACUAGUGGUGGGGGCGCUGCUGCAGGGGGUCCAGGGGUGAAUGGUCAUGCAGGGAGUAUGUUUGCCAUUACAAAACCUGGACUGUUUAGGGAGGAGGUGAUGAUUUUGGGGGGCCCUGAGAAGUGGACAAGCCGUCCGCAUGGAGCUGUUUGGGUGACUUGGAAGUUACUAUGAUCAGUUGGGGCUUGAAGUUGUGAGGUGUAAUUACACUGAUGGGGUGGUAGGUGCCCCAGGGGCAGGCCUGAUAACAGGUUGCAUUGGAUGCAUAAAGGGACAUGGAAAGUUAAGAUGGUAUUCAUAGUAACAGGGCCGUGUAUGCGCUUUUCAUUGCUUGUGUAAUAGAUGAGGUUGGAAAUGUAAGAACGUAAAAGUUGGAUUGCACGUCCUGUUAGGGUAUUCUUGGUCUUAUCAGAGAUGGGGAAGUUGGCUAAUGAUUGCAUAUUUAGAAGUUGGAAAGGGUCUUUUCCUUCAUAAUGAGGGUGAUAGGUUAAGUUGGUAGAGACCCAGGUUUUUGCAGGAAUGGGAGUGGCUACGUAAGCAGAGAUUGAUAGAUACAAAGCCAACAGUCAUUUGUGAGGGAAGGAUUGGACUGGUUUAACAGAGAGUGGGUUGAGAGUCUUGUAGAGGUAUUUAGGAGCUAGUGGAAGGGGAGGGGUGAUUGUAUGAGGUAUCCAAGGAAGCAGGAGGGAUAGAUAGUCAAAGAGUAAAUAGGAAGGUAAAGAGGGUGCUCUGGAAGACGAGAUCAUUUUAUCCAGGCUGAGUUAAAGGUAGGAGUAAAUUGCUGUCAGAAGGAAGGAAGAUAGAAAGAAGGUUGAUAAGAUUAGGAUUUUCGUCCUAGCAGGAGCUGUAGUAUAUAGCCCUAUCACAAAGAGUAUGGUUAGUAUGCUGCUUAAUCAUAUGAUGAAAUAGUAAAAGGAUUCCAUUAAAGGGUUAAGGAGAGGUGUUAAAGAUUAUGUAGGUUUUCACUUAUCUUUUUUAAGGAGGAAGGGGUUUUUCUUCAGGAUCAGUGGUAGGAGCCUUUUUAGUCUGGGAUAUUUCCUUCCAAAACAGGAGAUGCAAGUCCUCCAGUGGUUCGCAGGUGUAUCAAGGCUGGUCUGGCUGAUCUUGGGACUCCUGAGCUGAUGGUCCUGCAGGUUUCUCAGCGGGUGUCCAAAAUUUAACUCGGGUGUGGUGAAUCCAAGAUUCCACUCCUGCCACCUUAACUGCAGUGGGGGUAGAGAGGAUUACCGAGUGUGGUCCUUCCUACAAAGAGCCCAUGGAUGGGGAGGUAGAGGGGAGAGAUUUGACCAACACUAGAUCUCCUGGUUGAAACAACUCUGUUCCCUUUUCUCUGUGACAUCCUUCAGGUAGGAUUUUAAGGUUUUGUUGAUAUUUUGCCAAAGAAGUUAUAUCUUUGACGAAGUUGGCCGUUUCCUGAUGAAGUAGGACGUCAUUUGUGAGAAAAGGUCGUCCAUACAGCAUUUCAUAUGGACUGAGCCCCAUUUUGUGAGGAGAAUUUUGGAUUCUCAACAAGGCCAUGGGCAAAAGAGUAGGCUAUGGGAGAUGAGUUUCUUGUGUUAGUUUCCUUUAGUGCCUCUUGAGUGUUUUGUUUGCCUUCUCGACCUUCCCUGAGGAUUGUGGCCUCCAGGCGCAGUGAAGGUGAUAUUGUAUCCCUAGCGCCCUGGAAGGGUACCGAGUUACCACGGCUUUAAAAGCUGGACCAUUGUCGCUCUGUAAGCUUUGGAGAAGCCCAAAUCUAGGAAUUAUUUCAUGAAUUAGGACUUUAAUCACUUCCUGAGCCUUCUCUGUCUUGCGAGGGAAAGCCUUUAUCCAAUUUGUAGAGGUAUCAACACACACCAAUAAUUAUUGAAAUCCCUUCGACUUAGGCAUAUGGGUGAAGUCUAAAUGCCAGUCCUCUCCGGGCUAGUGACCUAUUCUUUGUUCCCUUAGAGGGGACUUAUGAUGGACCAAGGGAUUAUUCCUUUGGCACACCUCACAGACUUUGACUACCUGUCAGAUGGUCCGGAGGAGAUUUGGCCCUGUAAAUAGGGAUUUGGCCAUUUGAUGAGUGUUUUCAAUACCCAUAUGAAAAGUUUGUUGGAGGGUUUUAAGUAUUUUCCACUGGAUGGCUUUGGGUAUAAGUACCUUUCCUCCUUCUGUCAUUAACCACCCCGAGGGGAGACAACUAUGCCCCCGUGAAAGUCCCCAUUCUGUUUCAGUUGGGGAAUACUGGGGCUUAAUCUCUUGGAGGGGGUUGUUCCAUACCAAGGGUCCUUCCGUAGGUAUUUCUAAUGGGAGGUUCCUCCUGGCAGCAAUUUUGGCCUCAGCAUCUGCCCUGCGGUUUCCUUCUGCCUUUUCUCCUUCACUUCCUUCUGCCUUUUCUCCUUACACUUUGGCAGUGUAAGACUGCCACCUCCUUGGGUUUUUGCACUGCGUGCAAUGACUCCAUAAUUUCCUUGUGGUAUUUAAUGGGGGUUCCCUCAGAGGUUAGGAACUCCCUUUCUUUCCAUAUUGCAGCAUGGGCAUGUAGGAUUAGAUAAGCGUACUUGCUAUCUGUAUACACAUUUAUUCUUUUUCCCUUUCCCAAUUCCAAGUCUCGGUUAAGUGCCACUAGUUCUUCUAACUGGGCACUGGUCCCUGGGGGAAGAGGCUUACUUUCAAGUGUCGUUACAUCACUAACUAUGGCAUAACCUGCCCUUUGUAUUCCAUUGUCCACCAAUGAACUUCCAUUGGUAUACAGGUUAAGGUCAGGAUUAGUUAAGGGGACUUCCAAGAGAUCAUCUCGGGCAGCAUAAGUCUGGACUAUAAUUUGUUGGCAGUCAUGCUCGAUUGGUUCGCCAUCCUCUGGGAGAAAAGUGGCAGGGUUGAGGGCCACGCAUGUACAUAUUUGAAGCACUGGUCCCUCAAGGAGUAGUGCCUGGUAUCUGAGUAGGCGGUUGUCUGAUAGCCAUAAACUUCCUUUGGCACCUAGUAUGCCAUUUACAUCAUGAGUAGUCCAGACAGUGAGAUCCUUUCCUUGUGUUAUUUUGAUAGCCUCUGACGCUAAGACGGCCACCGCCGCAACUACCCUUAAACAGUGAGGCCAGCCUUUUGCUACUACAUCGAUUUCCUUAGUUAGGUAUGCCACCGGUUGUGGGGUUGUCCCACGAGUCUGAGUAAGGACUCCAAGAGCUAUUCCUGCUCUCUCUCUGAUAUAUAAAGAGAAGUUUUGUCCUGUGGGAAGGCUUAAAUCUGGAGCUUGUACUAGGUUCUGCUUUUUAAGGUUUUGAAGGCUGUUUCUGUCCCUGGUUCCCAUUCUACUAGAUGAAUAUUUGCCCUCUGGGUCUCCUUGAUUAGAGUAUGGAGGGGCCUGGCUAUCUCGCUGUAUCCGGCAGUCCAUAGUUGGCAAAACCCAGUGAUUCCAAGGAACCCCUGCAACUGUUUUAAUGUCUUAGGGUGAGGAUAAGCCAGUAUAGGCCGUACUCAUUCCUUUCUGAGGGCCCUGGUCCGUCUGGCUAAGAUUAGGCCUAGAUAUUUGACCUGCUAUAGGCAAAGCUGGGCCUUCAACCUAGAUGCCUUGUUCCCUUGAUCAGCUAGAAAGUUCAGGAGAUCUAGAGUAGCCCACUGACAUGAGGCUUCUGAACUGGUAGCCCAAAGUAAAUCAUCCACAUGCUGAAGGACCAGAGUGCCUGGACUUGAGAAGUGGCCUAGAUCUUGGGCCAAUGCCUGACCAAACAGGUGAGGGCUAUCCCUAAACCCUUGGGCCAAGACUGUCCAUGUAAGUUGGGAUGUGUGGUCUGUGGGAUCCUCAAAGGCAAAGAGAAACUGUGAGUCAGUGCAGGGGAAUACAGAAGGCGGCAUCCUUGAGGUCCAGAAUAGUGAAUCAUUCUGCUUCCUCUGGUAUUUGAGAGAGCAGGGUAUAGGGGUUGGGUACAACUGGAUAUAGAGGAAUUACUGCCUCAUUGAUGAGUCUAAGGUCUUGCACUAGUCUCCACUGACGAUUGGGUUUUUGUACCCCUAGAAUUGGGGUGUUGCAGGGACUGCUGCAUUUCCUUACUAAGCCUUGAGCUUUCAAAUGUUUAACAAUAUCCUGUAAUACUUUAUGAGCUUCAGGCCUUAAGGGAUAUUGCCUCUGAUAAGGAAAAGUGGUGGGAUCUUUUAGCCUGAUUUGGACUGGGUGGGCAUUUUUUGCCCUUCCAGAUUGUCUUUCCAAUGCCCAGACUUCAGGGUUGAUUCCCUCCUCAAGUAGGGGACAACAAAUGGGUAACUUGUUCCCCAUAUUCGUGUAGAUAAUAGCUCCAGCUUUGGCUAAUAUAUCCCUCCCUAAUAAGGGUGUGGGACUUUCAGGCAUAACAAGAAAGGCAAGUGAAAAGAGCAAAGUCUUCCAAUUACAACUGAGGAGGUGGGAGAAAUACCUGGUUACAGGCUGCCCCAGGAUUCCUCGGAUGGUAACAGACCUUGAGGAUAGUCGUCCAGGACUGGAGAUUAACACUGAGAAGGCCUCGCCAGUGUCCAAGAGGAAGUCAAUUUCCUGGCCCUCAAUGGUUAAAUGUACACGGGGCUCAGUGAGGGUGAUGACAAGAGCUGGCGCUUGCUCUGGGCACCGUCAGUCCUGUUGUUGGAUCAUCUGGUUGGGGGCUUCUGGCCCAGAGAACCAUUGCACUCUGGGGCAGUGCGCCUUCCAGUGAUUGCCUCGGCAUAGCGGACAUGGAUGAGGGGGUGGCUUCUCGUUGGACAGUCUUUUUUAAAGUGUCCUUGUAAACCACACUGAUAACAAGCCCUACUGGGUGAUUGGCCUUUUCCAUUUUCUGUCUUCUCUGAACCACCAAGGUUUGUCUGUCUGAGGGCCAUGACUAAGGCUGCUGCCUUUCUCUGAUCUCGCUUUUCCUUUUGGGCCUAUUCCUCUUGGUCCCUAUUAUAGAACACUGAGGUUGCCAGGUUUAGUAAUGCCUCCAGAUUUUGUUCAGGGCCCAGGGCUUGCUUUUGGAGCUUUCUCCUGAUAUCUGCGGCUGAUUGGGUAAUAAACUUAUCUUUUAGGAUCAAUUGACCCUCUAGGGAGUCGGGUGACAGGGUAGAGUAUUUUCUUAAGGCCUCCUGUAGCCAGUCGAGGAAGGCAGAAGGAUUUUCUUCCUUUCCCUGAGUUAUGCUAGACAUCAUUGAAUAAUUAAUGGGCUUUUUCCUAACUCUCCUUAGUCCUUCUAGAACACAGGUCAACAGAUGUUUAUGACUCCAGUCCCCAUGAUCUGAGUUGAGUCCCAGUGGGGAUCCAUACUGGGGACGACUUGCUGACCGGUAGGGAAUUUGUCCCUUUCUUCGGCUGUCAUUCUGUCAUUUACUUGACUAAGAUACCAGGUAUCACCAAACUCUCGGGCUGCAGCUAAAGCUGCAUUCUUUUCAUUAAAGACUAGGGUUUGAUCUAACAAUAGCAUGACAUCUCUCCAAGUGAGAUCGAAGGUUUGCCCUAGACCCUGUAGGAAAUCUAUCAGGAUCAUCUGAAAACUUCCCCAGGUCUGCCUGGAUCUGCUUUAAAUCAGAGAGGGAGAAGGGGACAUGUACCCAGCUUGGGCCAAAUUCCUCUCCCCCUACAGCUUGAAGGGGACAUAACCGAUAGCCCGGGGGUUUUUGUGGUCCCUUGGAGAUUUCUUUGCUUAUUUCCUUCUGGGCAGGGGAGAUUAGAGGAGGCUUAUCAUUAAUAGGAAGGGGAGCUAUAGGGAGGCUAGGAUAUGGGGGUAAGCUGAGAGGUCCUCCUGUGGGACAUAAAUUGCAAGCUUUGCAUAUUCUCCUUCAAUGAAAAGAAAGCUGGACAUAAGGUAUUUCAAUCCAUUUGCCUUCCCUCUUACAGAAAAGGUCAAGCUGCAGGAUAGUAUUGUAAUUUAUACUUCCCUCAGGUGGCCAUUUUUACCCAUCAGAGAGAGAAUACUGGGGCCAAGCCAUAGUGCAGAAAAAAAUAAGCUGCCUCUUUUUCAGGGUUUCUGGGUCAAAUUGGUCCGAAUGGCUUAGGAUGCAUUUCAAGGGUGAGCAUGUUGAUGCCUGAGUGUUUCCCAUCUGAAAGACAAAACCACCUGCAGUUUUGGUUUGUUUUUCUCCCCCUGCCCAAGAACCUAUAAUGGUCCCUGGACCCUGCUGAUCGGAAUAGUUGCGCUCACCGACGCAGCAGCAGAAACACCUCUUGCCCAAGAACCCUGGACCCUGCUGAUGGGAAUAGUUGUGCUCGCCGACGCAGCAGCAGAAACACCUCUUGCCCAAGAACCCUGGACCCUGCUGAUCGGAACAGUUGCGCUCACUGACACAGCAGCAGAAACACUAGUUUCCCUCCUAGACCACAAGGAGGACUGAGGAAGGUUGGAUUUAGUGGCCCUUACCGACGCAUUCUCGUAAAACCUGCACCUUGCCUGUCCUCCUAGACCACAAAGAGGACUGAGAAAAAUCAGAUUUAAUGACCCUUACUGACGCAUUCUUGAAAACCUGUUAAGAGUCCUAAGCGUUCUCCUGUUAGUAUUGGGACUUUACUUGUGUCCUAUAAAGAUGUUAUGCCCCCAAAAUGAAGUGGAGGGCCAUACCCUGAGGGAGAGAAGGGAUCUCCAGGGUUGGAAGAGUGAUGCCUUUUGUCCUCACUUAUAUGAAUAGGAAGGAUACAAUUUCUGAGGCUCCCCAUAUCCUAGCUUCAGGAAUAGCUUUUGUUAGGCCUGCUUGUCUGAGUAGGGGUGCUAAAAUUCCAGAUAGUACCCCCUAUGACAGGGCUUUGGGCAAAAAUUAUGUCUUUCUGAUUGGCGGGCCCGGGUGCCUAAAGAAGGGAACAGAGUCCUGAAACUAGAAAAGAACUAGAGACAGGGAGUGGUUUUUAGAAGCAGGACUAGCCUCAGAGAAGAGAGGUGAGAGGACGUUUGUCUGACAGGCAUUAGGACCCAGGAGGCAAGGGUCAGGAUGGAUAGGAUAGAUGGGCGAGUCUCACUUGGGCGACAUAACUUUGAGAGUUCCGCUCAUGGCCACAGGGUCAACCAGCUUGUUGUUGGGACCCCGGAGUUGAAUGGCUUUCCUCUCUGUUGACCGUUGGCUCAGCCUGGAAGUACAGGAGAAGUGGAAGCUGGUACCAGGCAAACCACCGCUCCCAACUCUGAAGAGUCGGGGGUUGUUAGCCCUUUCCCAGAAAGCCUGACACGCGUGUCUUUAGUCCGGUGGCUGUGCUAGUUGCUUUUAACUGGCCGACAGGUGCCUGGUAUUUAGCCCCCGAAUUCUACGGAAAAAUAGGACAGAAUAGCAAGCAAAAGGGGUCCGAUGAUACUCACUGCUUGGCGAUAGUCCCAUCUGGGUCGCCAAAAUGUGUCCAGAAUUGGUUCCUUCUGGUGGGUUCUUGGUCUCGCUGACUUCAAGAAUGAAGCCGUGGACACUCGCGGUGAGUGUUACAGUUCUUAAAGAUGGUGUGUCCGGAGUUUGUUCCUUCAGAUGUGUCCAUUCCUUCAGAUGUGUCCAGAGUUUCUUCCUUCCGGUGGGUUUGUGGUCUCGCUGACUUCAGGAGUGAAGCUACAGACCUUCGCAGUGGGUGUUACAGCUCUUAAAGGUGGUGUGUCCGGAGUUUUUUGUUCCUCCUGGUGGGUUCGUGGUCUUGCUGACUUCAGGAACGAAGCUGCAGACCCUUGCGGUGAGUGUUACAGCUCAUAAAGGUAGUGUGGACCCAAAGAGUGAGCAGCAGCAAGAUUUAUUGUGAAGAGCAAAAGAACAAAGCUUCCACAGUGUGGAAGGGGACCUGAGUGGGUUGCUGCUGCUGGCUUGGGUGGCCAGCUUUUAUUCCCUUAUUUGGCCCUGCCCACGUCCUGCUGAUUGGUCCAUUUUUACAGAGUGCUGAUUGGUGCAUUUACAAACCUUUAGCUAGACACAGAGCUCUGAUUGGUGCAUUUUUACAGAGUGCUGAUUGGUGUGUUUACAAACCUUUAGCUGGACACGGAGUGCUGAUUGGUUCGUUUUUACAGAGUGCUGAUAGGUGCGUUUACAAACCUUUAGCUAGACACAUAGUGCUGAUGGGUGUGUUUACAAUCCUUUAGCUAGACAGAAAAGUUCUGCAGGUCCCCACCCGACCCAGAAGCCCAGCUGGCUUCACCUCUCAAUAUCUCAUUGGUCAGAGAAAGUCAUGUGGCCAGGCCUGCCCCUGCCUGUAGGAAGCUGAUGGGCAUCACUGGGCUGGAUGUAGACUCCUCCUCGAAGGGCAGGGGGAGUGAAUGAAAGCAGCCAUACUGUCUGCUGCAGUGAGCCUGGGUUAGAGAGGCAGAGGAAGUUGGAACAUAGUGUACUGAAUGUGAAAAUUUAAGUUUGGGUCAAUAUCAGCUCUUAGAACUUUUGUCUGCUGAAGCCUUUUUAUUUUAGAAUAAUACUCUUUUUGAUUGAAGCUGUCCUGGAAACCACUGUGGAUAUUUCUGCUAGUAGUCGUCCUCUGGUCAGAGGUUUUCAUAUUUGGGAGCACAGGUGACUAUAAGCUCCCUGAUGUUGCCUGUGCAUACUUGUAAGGUUACCCUAAGGGCCUUAGCCUGCCAGAUGCUUGCUGGUGACCAGCCGAGCCCCAUCUUCCUCAUGUCCAAAUGAGUCCUCCUUUUGUCAGGUGUUAGUUCAGGAGGUAAACUUAAUAAUAAAUGUGGCUGCUUUGGUGUAACCAUAAAAUGAGGAAUAUGCUAAAAUAGAAUUCCUUUGGAGGCAUGGCAAAAAUUAAGGCUGGAAGUUGAGUCUGGGCCAGAUUGUAGAGCCUUUGAUGACUGGUUCCAGCAUCUUUGGCUUCAGUUUCUUCUGUGGGGUUAGGAGUUGGAGUGCUGGGUGCCCAGGAACAAUCAGCCUGGGCCUAGAGACUGGACAGCAGUGGGGAACGGGCACCAGACAGUGACCUCCUGAUAUGCCUGUUACAGAUGGUGGCCUUAGGUCCACAUUUGCAUGGGCUCACCCCUCUUCCUUUUUUCUGCUCCAAAGUCUGUGCCUCCAUUGGGAGCACAUACAGUUGUCACCCACUCUGUGAAGCCCUUUCUGACUCAUGUUACGGGUACUUGCUUUCUGCCGCCGUGGACUACUCGGUGACUCCUCCUCCUCUUCCUCAACACCUAGGGCGACUUUUCCCUACCAUCUUUCUGUGUCUGUGGACAUCACCUCUCUCGGCCCCUAGAUGGGAGGGGUCCUUACCAGCCUUGGGCUGCGGCCUCUCUGGGGAGAGCCCAGUGCCCUCCCUGCUGCAUCCUUCAUUUUCCUCCCGGUCAUCUCCAAGCCGAGCCUCCUUUCUCUGGAACCAAGUGUGGGAGAUGCAGUUGUGGUACAAAGGAAUGAAUGCCCACUUGCCUUAACUCAUUUUUUUUUCUCUUAUUGUCCUGUAGCCAGCUGCUGAAUUCCUCACCACUCACCUUCACCUUUCUCUCGUUUUCUGUUCAGCCAGCUCUCUUGACCCUGGUGCUUCCUUGCUCGAAAUCAUGUCUUUUUUUUUUUUUGACAAUACACUGUGUCAGAGGAAUCCUUGAGUUUUACAACUGGAAGUGACUUUAGAGGUUAGCUGAUUCAGCUUCUCUCCCUUCCCAGGUGAGGAACGGGACACCCACAGCUGUGUGGAGACUUAUCCACCCUGCAGGUGCCAGCUAAAUCCUUCAAAAUGACCUUUCCAAAAUUAACGCCAUGUUCUGACAUAGCCAAAACUGUAAUGUCUGUCAUACAUGACAAGACGUUUGAUGCAAAUGAUUUGUAUCAGGGGCAGAAUUUUAACAAGGUCCUCAGUUCCUUAGUGACUCUAAAUAAAGUAACAGCAGACAUCGGGCUGGGGAGUGACUCCGUGUGUGCCCGGCCCUCGUCUCACCGCAUAAAGUCUUUUGACUCCCUUGGAUCACAGUCUUUGCACACUCGGACUUCAAAACUGUUCCAGGGCCAGUAUCGGAGUUUGGACAUGACCGAUAAUAGCAACAAUCAACUGGUAGUAAGAGCAAAGUUUAACUUCCAGCAGACCAAUGAGGACGAGCUUUCCUUCUCAAAAGGAGACGUCAUCCAUGUCACCCGUGUGGAAGAGGGAGGCUGGUGGGAGGGCACACUCAACGGCCGGACCGGCUGGUUCCCCAGCAACUACGUGCGCGAGGUCAAGGCCAGCGAGAAGCCUGUGUCUCCCAAAUCAGGAACACUGAAGAGCCCUCCCAAAGGAUUUGAUACGACUGCCAUAAACAAAAGCUAUUACAAUGUGGUGCUACAGAAUAUUUUAGAAACAGAAAAUGAAUAUUCUAAAGAACUUCAGACUGUGCUUUCAACGUACCUACGGCCAUUGCAGACCAGUGAGAAGUUAAGUUCAGCAAACAUUUCAUAUUUAAUGGGAAAUCUAGAAGAAAUAUGUUCUUUCCAGCAAAUGCUCGUACAGUCUUUAGAAGAAUGCACCAAGUUGCCCGAAGCUCAGCAGAGAGUCGGAGGCUGCUUUUUAAACCUGAUGCCACAGAUGAAAACCCUGUACCUCACGUAUUGUGCCAAUCACCCUUCUGCAGUGAAUGUCCUCACGGAACACAGUGAGGAGUUGGGGGAGUUCAUGGAGACCAAAGGUGCCAGCAGCCCUGGGAUUCUCGUGCUGACCACGGGCCUGAGCAAACCCUUCAUGCGCCUGGAUAAAUACCCUACGCUGCUCAAAGAGCUCGAGAGACACAUGGAGGAUUAUCAUACAGAUAGACAAGAUAUUCAAAAAUCCAUGGCUGCCUUCAAAAACCUUUCAGCCCAAUGUCAAGAAGUCCGGAAGAGGAAAGAGCUUGAGCUGCAGAUCCUGACGGAAGCCAUCCGGAACUGGGAGGGCGAUGACAUUAAAACUCUGGGCAACGUCACUUACAUGUCCCAGGUCCUGAUUCAGUGUGCCGGAAGUGAGGAAAAGAAUGAAAGAUAUCUUCUACUCUUCCCAAAUGUUUUGCUAAUGUUGUCUGCCAGUCCUAGGAUGAGUGGCUUUAUCUAUCAGGGAAAGCUUCCAACGACAGGAAUGACAAUCACAAAGCUUGAGGACAGUGAAAAUCAUAGAAAUGCAUUUGAAAUAUCAGGGAGCAUGAUUGAGCGGAUAUUAGUGUCGUGCAACAACCAGCAGGAUCUGCAGGAAUGGGUGGAGCACCUACAGAAGCAAACGAAGGUCACGUCUGUGGGAAACCCCACCAUAAAGCCUCAUUCAGUGCCAUCUCAUACCCUCCCCUCCCACCCGGUCACUCCGUCCAGCAAGCACGCAGACAGCAAGCCCGCGCCGCUGACGCCCGCCUACCACACGCUGCCCCACCCCUCCCACCACGGCACCCCGCACACCACCAUCAACUGGGGACCCCUGGAGCCUCCGAAAACACCCAAGCCCUGGAGCCUGAGCUGCCUGCGGCCCGCGCCUCCCCUCCGGCCCUCAGCUGCUCUCUGCUACAAGGAGGUGAGGUCCCUUGACCACUCAAACAGCCAGAUGACGGAUCUUAGUAAGAGCCCUAAGACCAUGAAAAAGCUGCUGCCCAAGCGCAAACCUGAACGGAAGCCUUCAGAUGAGGAGUUCGCGUCCCGGAAAAGCACAGCUGCUUUGGAAGAAGAUGCUCAGAUUCUGAAAGUCAUUGAAGCUUACUGCACCAGCGCCAAAACAAGGCAAACACUCAAUUCAACAUGGCAAGGCACUGACCUGAUGCAUAAUCACGUCUUGGCUGAUGAUGACCAACCAAGCCUAGACUCCCUGGGGCGUCGCAGUAGCCUUUCUCGUUUGGAGCCUUCAGACCUCUCGGAAGACUCUGACUAUGACAGUAUAUGGACAGCCCAUAGUUACAGAAUGGGUUCUACAUCUCGUUCACGCAAAGAAUCUGCUCCACAAGUUUUGCUUCCAGAAGAAGAGAAAAUUAUAGUGGAAGAAACUAAAAGUAAUGGUCAGACAGUGAUAGAAGAAAAGAGUCUUGUGGAUACCGUAUAUGCAUUAAAGGAUGAAGUUCAAGAAUUAAGACAGGACAACAAAAAGAUGAAGAAAUCUCUAGAGGAAGAACAGAGAGCCCGCAAAGACCUGGAGAAGCUGGUGAGGAAAGUCCUGAAGAACAUGAAUGAUCCUGCCUGGGAUGAGACCAAUCUAUAAGGGAUGUCCUCAGUUCUUUCUGUUGAAGACCAGUUCUGAGGUGAAGCUGGGCACCCCUGACCCAAGUCGGGGUGCACUCAGGACCACAGGGCAGGGCUGGGUGGGGCGCCACCUUGCUCUCUGUAUAUAGAAAAGCUGGAGCUUAUUCUGCGAAUGGAGACGAUCAAACCAUGACUGAUGAAUCCAGACAGGAGGGAUUGACUCUGAGGACCUGAGCUACAUCAAUCCACUCUGUGAACAUCUCAGUUACCUCAUUCUGCAAUAAGUUCAGUGACUGACUAAAAGUCUUGUUUUUCCAGACUUUGAAUUGAAUAUAUAAAUAUUAUAUAUACAUGUUUCUUGUAAAUAUCCCAUUUUGAAUGCAUACCUGUGGUGGUUCUGUCCGGGCUAAUCCCCAUGCUAGAAUGUCCUUUCCAGCUACGUGAAUAAGAAGUCCCAUGCCCGCAUCCACCGGAAGCAGAAGCCUGGUGGAUGCCUGGUUCGUUCCGCAGCACCAGGGCCUCCACCGUGCUGUGGCAGCACCCCCCAUGUCGGUAUUUCUAAAUAACCUUAUUUAUACCUGCAGAGAUACACUUCAGUCCCAUUCAGAAGUCUUCUCUUAAAGCAGCAUUACAGUCCCAGACCUGCGGGUUUCUGAGGGCAACUUGCUGGCUGACAGACUCAGUCUUGACCUCAAGGAAGGCCCAUACGGCACUGCCGCAUCCACCUAGAGGUGUUUGCUCUUGUCCGCUGUCUGAGUACUGUGAUUCUCAGAUGAGUUUGCUGCGUUUUGGGAGGACACAGACGGUUCUGUAUAGGCUAGUUCAGUAACAACAAAAUACACUGUUUUGUCUUCCCUCAAAGAGAGAUCUUACUAGAACCUGUAAAUAGAAUGUAUUAUUUAUUAUAAGUCACUGCAGCUGAUGAAAACAGAUGGAGGCCAUGCUGCAGGCUGAUACUGAUGGGUGGAGUUUUGUCAUCAGGCCAGCCUCAUCCCGAGGUCUCCUCCACCAUUGGCCGUAGCCAGCAGGCUUCAGUGCUCACCGAAAGUAAAAUCCCCUCCUUCAGCAAGAAUAAAGCAAUAUACACCUUAGGUUCCACUAAGUAACAUAGGCAUAAGCAGGGAACGUUUCCCCCACUGUGUUCCAGUGCAGAGGAGACGAAGCCUGUCCUCACCGCGGCUCGCUGGGCCCAGGCUGGCUCUGGAAAGCCUGUGCGGUCCUGGGCAGGAAGCCCGGCCCGUGGAGCAGGUUUUCGUUCUGCUUCAGCAAUAAAUAAGGGUGACCACAGGGACUUUGCUUUUGGUUUCCUUUCCUGUGAAAAGGUUGGUUUUAAAGUGAGAUACACUUUUCCGUAGAACAAGUGUUCUAUCUUUAAAAACCCAAAUUGCAGCACCGUGGAUUACUGGUCUCAGAACAACUCAUUGCGCAUCAGAUUUGACUCUCUGAUUUUCUGUCUAUUGGCCAAAUUGCCCUUUAACUGCACCUGAAUCCUUUGUGUACUGAUGCCUUUGAGCUGGGCACCUUGGGAGAGUGUUGUGUUGCUGUUUACGGUUCUUCCUUGCCCUUGCUAAUUACAGUCUCUGGUGCCCAGCAAGCCCCUUUGGCUUCCUUCCGUGACUGGUCACGUUGUCUGCCUGGGCUCAGCGUGGACCUGCCCCAUGCUGCAGAACCUGGCCUCACCUGGACUUUUCACUAGAAUUGCCAGCUUCCUCAACUUAGCAGAUCAUUCACUCAUGCGGGCACAAGCAAAGAUCAACACUUUCUUUUUUGGUAAGCUUGAGUUUUACAAGUUAUUUUUUGGUGAUGCGUAAGACAUUGCAGUGGGAAACCAUUCAACUUGAGUUUAUUGGAGUUUGCUGUUGUAGCAGGUUUUAACUCAGGAACAACUCUUGUCUGAUCUCUCCGCCCCUCUGCCGGGAGGCGACAUUAACUGUCCUCUCGGAGCCGGUAGCGUUGCUGUCCGAGUCCCCAGGACGGAUCUCCUGCAGACCUGCCUUAAUGCUCAGAUCGAAGUAUUUCACAAGAAUACUUGUGUUUUUAACAGCCCUUCCCCUGGACGGUGCGGCCAUGAGGGCCUCAUGUUACGGCAUUGCCUUUUCUUUCUGUGGAUCCAGUAUCUUCCUCGGCUUUUUAGGGAGCAGGAAAAAUGCGUCUGAGAGCAACUCUUUUUAAAAACCUGCCCUGUUGUAUAUAACUGUGUCUGUUUCACCGUGUGACCUCCCAAGGGGGUGGGAACUUGAUAUAAACGUUUAAAGGGGCCACGAUUUGCCCGAGGGUUACUCCUUUGCUCUCACCUUGUAUGGAUGAGGAGAUGAAGCCAUUUCUUAUCCUGUAGAUGUGAAGCACUUUCAGUUUUCAGCGAUGUUGGAAUGUAGCAUCAGAAGCUCGUUCCUUCACACUCAGUGGCGUCUGUGCUUGUCCACAUGCGCUGGGCGUCUGGGACCUUGAAUGCCUGCCCUGGUUGUGUGGACUCCUUAAUGCCAAUCAUUUCUUCACUUCUCUGGGACACCCAGGGCGCCUGUUGACAAGUGUGGAGAAACUCCUAAUUUAAAUGUCACAGACAAUGUCCUAGUGUUGACUACUACAAUGUUGAUGCUACACUGUUGUAAUUAUUAAACUGAUUAUUUUUCUUAUGUCACA